CUAAAGCCUUUUUACCCACUUUUUACAACAUGGCCUCUUAGUACCCAUUAACUCUCCCAUCCUUCCCUUUCAAAAACCAGACAAGUCCUACAUAUUAGUUCAAGACCUUCGUCUCAUCAAUCAGAUUGUACUUUUCAUCCAUUCUAUAGUGCCAAACCCAUAUACUCUCUUGUCCAGAAUACCUCCCACCACUACCUAUUAUUCCGUUCUCAGCCUAAAAGAUGCCUUCUACACCAUUCCCCUACAUCCCUCCUCUCAACCUCUUUUUGCCUUCACCUGGACUGACGCUGACACCCAUCAGUCCCAACAACUAACCUGGACCAUUCUUCCCAGGGCUUCCGGAAUAGCCCUCAUUAUUUUAGCCAAGCCCUUGCCUGCGACCUACUCUCUUUUCAGCCUUCCUUUUCCUACCUCAUCCAGUAUGUCGAUGAUCUCUGCAGUCUCUCCUAGGAAUCCUCCCAACAGAAUAUCCUCCUACUCCUUCAGCAUUUAGACUCUAAAGGGUACCGAAUGUCCCCUUCUAAAGCUCAAAUUUCUUCCCCUUCUGUUAUUUGUCUCAGCAUAAUUCUCCAUCAGCACACCCGCACUCCCCCCGCUGACCGUAUUCACCUAAUCUCCUAGACCCCAGUCCCUUCAAAAACAGCAGCUUCUCUCCUUCCUAGGCAUCAUUGGGUACUUCCACCUCUAGGUACCUGGUUUUGCCCUCUUAACAAAACCCCUUUAUAAGCUUACAAAAGGCAACCUAGCUGACCCCAUAGACCCCAAACCUUCCCUCAUUCAUCCUUUCACUCCCUGAAAAAAGCUCUUGAGACAGCCUCCUCACUGGCGUUCCUCGACUCCACCCAGCCCUUCUCUCUACAUGGCAGAGGUAAAGGGAUGUGCAGUUGGGGUCCUAACACAAGGGCCAGGCCCACGACCAGUGGCCUACUUAUCUAAACUUGACCUCACAGUCCUAGGCUGGCUGCCCUGUUUACAUGCUGCAGCGGCCACUGCCCUAAUACUCCUAGAAUCCCUCAAAAUCACUGGUUACACCCCAGUUACCCUCUAUAGCGCUCACAACCUCCAGAGUCUCAUUUCUUCCUCUCACCUCACACAACUACUCUCCUCCCAUCUCCUCCAGCUUUAUUCACUCUUUAUUUUAAACCCCAUGCUAACCAUUGCUCUUGGACCCAGUUUCAACCCAGCCUUUCACUUAGCACCCAACACAUGUCCUGAGCCACAUGACUGCAUCUCCUUAAUACACAUGGCAUCCUCCCCCUCUCCUCACAUUUCUGUUUUUCCAGUCCCAAACCCAGAUCACACUUGGUUUAUUGAUGGUAGUUCUUCAAGACCCAACCAAUUUUCGCCAGCCAAGGCAGGUUAUGCUAUUUGUUGUGUCCCACACAUCUGUUAUCGAGGCUGCUGCACUUCCACCCUCCACCACCUCUCAGCAAGCUGAACUAAUUGCUUUAACUCACGCUGUCUCUCUCUAAGGGAAUGCACGUCAAUAUUUAUACUGAUUCCAGGUAUGCUUUCCACAUCCUUCAUCACAGUGCUGCCAUCUGGGUGGAAAGAGGUUUUCUAACCACACAAGGGUCUUCCAUUAUCAAUGCCUUUCUCAUAAAGGCCCUCCUUAAGGCUGCUCUUCUGCCAGCCAAGGCUGGAGUUGUCCACUGCAGAGGAUGCCAAAAACCAACAGACCCUAUCACUAAAGGAAAUGCCCAUGCCAGUAAAACAGCAAAAGAGGUGGCAAACACCUCAGUGUCUGCAGACGUUCCAGUCUCUGCUCCAAAAGACCAGUAUAUUUCUUUCUCAUCUAUUAUCCCUACCUACUACUCUUCUUCUGAAAACCUGCUCUGCUAGUCCUUUCCAACUCACAAGGCAAGUGGUUCUUAGAUCAUAGAAAGUUCCUUCUUCCUGCCUCACAAGCGCAAUCUAUUCUCUUAUCCCUCCAUGACCGCUUCCAUGUAGGAUACAAGCCUUUGGCUCGCCUCCUAGAGCCCCUUAUUUCUUUCUCAUCAUGGAAGUCCGUCCUUAAACAAUCACUUCUUAAUGUUCUGUCUGCCACUCCAAGGUUUUCUUAGGCCCCCUCCUUCCCCAGCACAUCAGGCCUGAGGGUUUACUACUACACAAGAUUGGCAAAUUGACUUCACUCAUAUGCCUCGUGUCAAAAAAUAUAAGUACCUCCUAGUUUGGGUUGAUACCUUCACCAGAUGGGUCGAGGCCUUCCCUACUGGAUCUGAAAAGGCUGCAGCAGUUUUUACCUCUCUUCUAACAGAUAUUGUUACCUGUUUCGGCCUCCCUACUUCCAUCCAAUCUGACAGUGGUCCAGCCUUCAUUAGCCAAAUCACCCAGGCAGUUUCCCAGGCCCUUGGCAUCCAGUGGAAUCUCCACACCCCAUACCAUCCUCAUUCCUCAGGAAAGGUUGAAAGAGCCAACGGCCUCUUAAAAACUCACCCUCCAACUCCGAAAGGACUGGACUGUUCUCCUACCACUUGUGCUUCUCAGGAUCUGAGCCACCGCCCAUGAACCUACCAGGUAUAGCCCAUUCGAACUCUUAUAUGGUAGUACUUUUCUACUGGGGCCCAACCUCAUCCCAGACACCAGUCCUCCAACAGGCUAGGAAUGAAAUCUGUCAGGCUGCUAACCUUCUUUUACCCACCUCAGAUACCCAGCCAUAUGAGGACACUCUGGCCAGACAGCCCAUCCUGAUAAAGAGCUUAACCCCCUGAUCUCUACAACCUCAGUGGACAGGACCCUUCCUGGUCGUUUAUGGUACCCCAAUGGCUGUCUGCUUACAAGAUCCUCCUCAGUGGAUUCACCCUUCCAGAGUAAAGCUGUGUCCAUCUGACACUCAGCCUGACCCUUCUUCCUCCUCUUGGAAGUCGCAAGUACUCUCCCCGACCUCGUUAAAACUCACCGAAAUCCCUGAAGAAACUUAAAUGUCCUGCUCCUGUCCGCCCUGCUUCUUCACCCUCUUCCUCCACUCUAUUUGCCAAGACAUCUCCUGGUUUCAUCCCCAAACUCCCACCUUAGAUUCUCUCUUAAACUGGAUAGAUGAUCUCAUCUUUUAGGGCACUCUGUAUAACUUCUUCCCAGAUGAGACGCCUCUGUUUACCUUCCUACUCACUCUUUAUCUAUCCCUCCUGCUCCUUUGGCUACCUGGCAUGGCCGCACUCCCACUUCCAGUAAUGCCUAAUUACCUCUACAAAACUCUCAACCCACUCUCUGUUAAACCAGUCCAACCCUUCUUUGGCAAAGGACGCUGGCUUUGCAUUUCUCUAUCAGCUACCACUUACGUUGCCACUCUCAUUCCCACAAAAAACUGGGUAGUUACUAGCUUAACCUACCACCCUCGUAAUGAAGGAAAAAGCCCCUUCUAACUCCUACAUAUGCAGUCAUUGGCCAACUUCUCCAUCAAUGAAAUGACCGAAAAUACCCUGACAGGUCGUGCAGUUCAACUUUUACGCUCCUACAUGUCCAGCCUCACCCAUUACACAAGUAAUGAAAAGCCCAUACACGGCCCUGUGACUACAAACGCUGUCUUAACUUUCCAAGCCCCUUUAUGCAUCCAACACAACCUGUCAUCAGGCCUACCUCUAGGUCACCUACUGUUCCAUCAGUGCAACUACGCCUUGCAGCUUCAAGCCCCAACUGACUGUAUUAACUUCCAGGUCUCCCAAACAGCUACAUUCAAACAGCCUGUCCGCUUCUCAAAGCCCCCAGAAGUCAUCAGCACCUCUCUGCUUAACAAACAAUCCGGGUUUUGUAAUGGCAGGCAUACGCACUGCAUGACCAUUCACCCCUGGACCUCCUGCAGCAGCACUCCCACCACUGACGAAUGCCUCCUUAUCCCCUCUUUCGAUUACCCUUCUGAGUGGCUCCUAGUAGAUACAAAAUGAUUUUUCCUCCAAUGGGAAAAUAAAACACAGGGAGCCACUCAGCUUAUCCCAAACAUCCCUUUUCAGCCGCUCACUGGGGCCGCCUUGGCAAGUACCCUAGGGGUGUGGGAAAAUGAAAACAAAUUCACACACCUUUUUAACAUACACAGCCAGUUCUGCCUACCCAGCCAAGGCAUAUUCUUCUUGUGUGGAACUUCAACCUAUGUCUGCCUCACCACUAACUGGACAAGCACCUGUACCCUAAUCUUCCUAAGCCCCAAAAUUGACAUUGCCCCUGGAAACCAAACCUUACCAGUCCCUGUCAGAGCCCAAGUCCAUCAGCAUAGGGCUGUGCAGAUAAUACCCUUGCUUAUAGGACUAGGAGUUACCAAUGCCACAGGAACUGGAAUAGCAGGUUUGUCCCCUUCCCUGUCCUACUAUCAUACACUCUCAAAGGAUCUCUCAGACAGCCUACAAGACAUAGCAAAAUCCACCCUUACUCUCCAAUCCCAAAUAGACUCCUUAGCAGCAGUAACUCUGCAGAACCACCGUGGCUUAGACCUCCUAACCGUCGAAAAAGGUGGGCUAUGCACCUUUUUAGGGGAAGAUUGUUUUUCCACCAACCAGUCUGGACUAGUACGAGAUGCUGCCUCGCAGUUAAAUGAAAAGGCUUCUAAAAUCAGACAAUGUCUUUCAGACUUUUAACACCAAUCUUUGGAGCUGGGCGUUGUGGCUUCUCCCUAUAGCUGGGCCCCUCAUUUCCAUCAUUCUCCUUCUCCUAUUUGGACCCUGCCUCUUCCGUCUAGCCUCUCAGUUCCUACAAAAUCUCAUUCAAGCUAUUACCAAUCAAUCUAUGCGACAAAUGCUACUCCUAACUGCCCCUCAAUGUCACCCCCACCCCAAGAUCUCUCUCCCAAUUAGGAGUCCAUGCCGCCCCAAGUCCCGCUCGAAGAAUCCCUGAGAAACAUCACCCCGUCCACUUCUUUUCUUAUUAAAACAAAAAGACAGGAAUGUCAUAUCCCACAAAUAUGGCUGCAUUAUUGCCAGCAGGCCAUUAUUGACGGUGGGCCAUUAAGAACUCUGUGACCAGCACAUAUGCCUCCAGACUUCCUGGAACCAGAAAACCUGCAACAACCAAAAACCACAAAAGAAGAACAACGGGUUUCUGUUCCAACUGGUUGAUCAACUUCUUGAGUCAACAAGUCCCAAAACCAUGUUGUAAUUUUCCACCCGCCACUUUGCCCUGUAAAGACUGCUCUCCCUCACACCUCCGGGCUGACUCCCUUUUCCGAUUCAGCCCACUAACACCCAAGUGAAUAAACGGCCUUGUUGCUCACACAAAGUCUGCUUGGGUCUUCAAUCCAGACCACGCUGUAACACACACUUACAAAAUUCUGCUGAGAAUAUGCCCCCCGUUAUUCAUAAUGCUCAUGUUUUUCAUACUGAGGGUAGCUGUGCACUUUGGGUUUUUACAGAGAAAUGUGUUUUAGGGGAAGUUUUUCUGGCUGACUUGUUCAAUCAUAUCUAAUCUGAGUUUUUUUCUUAAGAUGCUUUUCUUUUUUUUUCCCUCUCAAUAUAAUCAUUUUCAGAGUGAGCUGUUUUUCUCUUGAAUGCAUUGGGUGUCUGUUUUGGAAGCCCUAUUACUAUCCCAUGGUGUCUGUUAAUGAGGUGGGCUGUCAUAGUGAGAACUCUUGGAGCUAUCUCUAUAUGGACUCAUGCUGGAAAUCCAGCAGAGUGAUUUCCAUGUCACCAUUACAAAUAAAAAACUGAGGCUUAAACACUGCACCCAUUCCCAUUAUUGUGAAGGUGCAAUUCUACCCAGGAGGCCUGCAGGCUCUCCUCCUGCAACUCAGGCUUCAUUCUCUGAUGUGGCAUUGAAGUGCUGCUGUGGCAGUUGGGGUUAUAUAUAGGGUGCCAGGUGUGAGCUGUGUGCUGGGGGCUCUGCCUCAGUGGCAGAUGGUAGGAGUCAAGAGAGGACACAAGCUACCAGGAGACGGCAAGCAGGAGGCACCUGGCUUUAAGUUGCAAAAUUACCUUUUGUCAUGAAGAUGUGAAAAGUGUAUUUUGUCAUUGAUUAUAACCAAUUAGCAUAUAUGGAUGACCUCCCAAAUUACCAGGUGAAUUUAUGAUGAACUAUGUAUGACAUGUGCUGUAAAUUUUUCUACUUGUGGACUAAUUAUUGUGACCGUCUUUCUGUCUUUGCAAUCUCUUAAGCAGAUUGACUGUGAUGCAUGUCACAUUCUGGUUGAAUUGUGUAAUAAAACAGCUUUCUUUCUGUUCUAUCAUUGUGGAGUUACUCUGGAGCUGGAGAAAAUUUUUCUUUUAUUUAUAUUUUCCAAACACUGUCUAGAAUUACCACACAUGAUAUAAACAUAUAAGGUGCCAACCAAGCUUUAAUCCAGAGGAGGCUUUUCCUUUCAGGCUUCCAGUCAACUCACAAUUGUGCUGCAAAAUGCAUGCUGUCCCCUAAAUAUGCAGGCAGAAUUGUGUCUCUGUCUAUUUGGUGUUAUAGUCCUCUACAGUCACCUCUAGAGAGCUAGGCCAGAUUUCUACAUACUUCACAGGGCAGCAGUUAACCAUUUUACCUCUUUCAAUGACUCUUGUAUCUUUAGACCAGAAACUGCUUCAGAGAUCAUGGGACCCAGAAACCCAGAGUAACGUGUGCCUUAAGUAGACAUGAGAAUCUCCAUAUUUUUUCCCUUCCUCCUCUUUUUUUUUUUUUUUUUGACAUGGGUUCUCACUCUGUUGCCCAGGCUGGAGUGCAGUGGCAUGAUCUCGGCUCACUGCAACCUCCACCUUCUGGGUUCAAAUGAUUCUUCUGCCUCAGCCUCCUGAGUAGCUGGGAUUACAAGCACGCACCAAGACGUACAGCUAAUUUUUGUAUGUUUAGUGGAAGGGGGGGUUUCACCAUGUUGGCCAGGCUGGUCUCAAACUCAUGACCUCAGGUGAUCUGCCUGCCUCGGCCUCCCAAAGUGCUGGUGUUACAGGUAUGAGCCACCACACCCAACCCCUUCUUCCUCUUCUUAAAAUACCCACAAAUGUGUGGAUGACACCUACUGCUACUGCACCCAUCCAGGAACUAAAUUUGCAGCUCCAAAUUCUGAAUCAGGGUCUUAAGAUUUGGGAAAAAAUAAAACCUUUUAUCUGAGAAAUGCAAAUUCUUUUAGUUAUAAGGUUCAGAGACAUUAAAAUAAUACCACAAUUAUGUAUUUCUCUGUUCUUUGAGCUAAGAAUUUAUCUCUUGAAACUGCUUGCUAUUGCCACAAGUAGGUAUAAAUUAAACUAAUAAUGACACACUGGAUCCUGUAACCCACACCCUAUAGCUUAACAAUGUUUAUCCAAUCAAUAAUCAAUCUUAUUUUUUUGUAAACAAAUGAGAGUUUCUGACAAACAACUUUGUAUCAGCCCACCCUCUUUCCCUCUCUUUUUGCCUUUACAAAUCCACUUGCAGCUGCGCUAAUCAAAGUGUAGAUUCCUGGCAACAUGAAUCUUUGAUCCCAGGUUACAAUUCCCAAUCUUGGCUCAAAUAAACUCUCUACUUAUAUUCAUGUAGCUUCAGCUUUUUCCUUUCAAGUAGACAUAUUAUUUAGAAUGUGCUAGAGCAGCCUCUAUGAGGCGAUCUCUCCUUUGGUUGUGCUCCACUUGCUGUAACACCCAAAAAUGCAGAGGCAGGCUGCUCCCACCUAGAAUCUGUACAUAAGGUCUGGCCUCUCCCUGGAAUUUACAAGACAGGGCCAGACUCUGGUUUGAGAAAGUACAGAAAACCAACAGGAGACAUUUUCUGCAUUGUGAGAUGUCAACAUAGACAUCUUAAAGCUUCCCUUUGAGAGUGUUGCUCUUAGAACUUUUCAGAUCUUGUUCAGUGACCUGCUACAGUUAUGUGAGAGGAUCCAGGUGUAAAUAGAAUCUGAUGACAGAUUCUGUAAGCGUAAACAAGCAUCUUAGGGGUGAGAGAUGAAGGCCACAAAGUAUCGAGAGUCAUGAUCACAAUUAUACCUACCCGUAAAAUGUAAUACUGGACUAGAGUAUUUUUUCUUUCCUUUUGCCCAAGAGCUAGCUAAUUAGGACCCGUAAUCUGGAGCUCCACUGUGGCAGUUCCACUUUCUAUUUAGAAUCAGCCUGAGUCUCUCCUGCCUGCCUUAUCCUUGGCCAUCAGCCCAGGGUCACUGGGAACUCUCUCACAAUCACCUAGGCAUCUUUGAGAUAUUUGAGGAUGUCCAGAGCAGAAUUGUGUCAGGUUGACAAGAGUGGUUAAUUCUGCCUCUGUCUCAGUGUAAGAGAAAUGAGACAUCCUGUGUUUGCUCCUCCCCUCAUACAAGAGAUGUCUUUGGUUGGUAUCCAGUUGAGAGUUUCCCAGUUUCCUGAUAGUUGGAUGAAAAACAAGGAGGAGGUCUGGAGACUCAAGCAGAUAAACUAAUUGCUACCAUUUCAUAUGGCCCUUAGAAAAAUAGAUAAAGCAGUCAUGGUCCCUACCAUCUAGGAACUGUUAGUCUAGACUAGCAACUGAAUACGUGGUUGAAUUAAGCAUCAUAUGGUUGGCAAAGUGAAUAGAUGUGUGGGAAAACGUGUGGGCUUUAUUUGGGCCACUUUCUUUAUAUCGUUGUGACUUCUGAGGUCAUCAUUUGAAUGAAUGUUUAUGACCACAAGAGUUUUAAAUAUUUUUAUUUCUUUUACUUUGCUAAGAAUACAUAUUUAUCUUAUAAUAAAAUUACCCUAGAAAACCCCAGGAGAUUUGUUUAAAUGGCUAAUUAGUAUAUUUACACAGUUGAUGGGUUGAGCAGAGUAAUAUAUAGGGUUUACUCCCAGCUGCAGUUCUGUUCAGAUUCACCCUUUUUGGAGGCUUUAUUUAGGUCUGGCCCCACCCUGGAGUCUUGCCUCACAGAACUGAUUAGAAGAGAUCAGAGUUUUGGCUGGUGCCUUUCCGGAGUGGUUGCUAACAAUUCCCGAAUUCCACAAGGAGAUAAAUGGGAAAAAAAGGAACCACUGACAUUUAAAGAUGUCGCCAUAGAAUUCUCUCUGGAGGAGUGGCAAUGCCUGGAUACUGCACAGCGGGAUUUAUAUAGGAAUGUGUUGUUAGAGAACUACAGAAACCUGGUCUUUUUGGGUAUUGCUGUCUCUAAGCCAUAUCUGAUCACCUGUCUGGAGCAAAAAAAAGAGCCCUGGAAUAUAAAAAGACAUGAGAUGGUAGCCAAACCCCCAGUAAUGUCUUUUCAUUUUGCCCAAGACCUUUGGCCAGAGCAGAACAUAAAAGAUUCUUUCCAGAAAGUGACACUGAGAAGAUACGGAAAAUGUGAAUAUGAGAAUUUACAGUUAAGAAAAGGCUGUAAACAUGUGGAUGAGUGUACGGGGCACAAAGGAGGUCAUAAUACAGUUAACCAAUGUUUGACAGCUACCCCAAGCAAAAUAUUCCAGUGUAAUAAAUAUGUGAAAGUCUUUGAUAAAUUUUCAAAUUCAAAUAGAUAUAAGAGAAGACAUACAGGAAACAAACACUUCAAAUGUAAAGAAUGUAGCAAAUCAUUUUGCGUGCUUUCACAACUAACUCAGCAUAGAAGAAUUCAUACUAGAGUGAAUUCCUACAAAUGUGAAGAAUGUGGAAAAGCCUUUAACUGGUUCUCAACUCUUACUAAACAUAAGAGAAUUCAUACUGGAGAAAAGCCCUACAAAUGUGAAGAAUGUGGCAAAGCCUUUAACCAGUCCUCACAACUUACUAGGCAUAAGAUAAUUCAUACUGAAGAGAAACCCAACAAAUGUGAAGAAUGUGGCAAGGCCUUUAAACAGGCCUCACACCUUACUAUACAUAAAAUAAUUCAUACUGGAGAAAAACCUUACAAAUAUGAAGAAUGUGGCAAAGUCUUUAGCCAGUCCUCACACCUUACUACACAAAAGAUACUUCACACUGGAGAGAACCUCUACAAGUGUAAAGAAUGUGGAAAAGCUUUUAACCUAUUCUCAAAUCUUACUAACCAUAAGAGAAUUCAUGCUGGGGAGAAACCCUACAAAUGUAAAGAAUGUGGCAGAGCUUUUAACAUAUCCUCAAACCUUAAUAAACAGGAGAAAAUUCAUACUGGAGGGAAACUCAACAAAUGUGAAGAAUGUGACAAAGCUUUUAACCGAUCCUUAAAACUUACUGCACAUAAGAAAAUUCUAAUGGAAGAGAAACCCUACAAAUGUGAAGAAUGUGGCAAAGUCUUUAACCAGUUCUCAACUCUUACUAGACAUAAGAUAAUUCAUACUGGAGAGAAACCCUACAAAUGUAAAGAAUGUGGCAAAGCUUUUAACCAAUCUUCAAACCUUACUGAACAUAAGAAAAUUCAUACUGCAGAGAAAUCCUAUAAAUGUGAAGAAUGUGGCAAAGCUUUUAACCAACACUCAAACCUAAUUAACCAUAGGAAAAUUUAUUCUGGAGAGAAACCAUACAAAUGUGAAGAAUGUGGAAAAGCUUUUAAUCGAUCCUCAACCCUUACUAGACAUAAGAAAAUUCAUACUGGAGAGAAACCCUACAAAUGUGAAGAAUGUGACAGAGCUUUUAGCCAGUCUUCAAACCUUACUGAACAUAAGAAAAUUCAUACUGGAGAGAAACCCUAUAAAUGUGAGGAAUGUGGCAAAGCUUUUAACCGAUUCUCAACCCUUACUAAACAUAAGAGAAUUCAUACUGGAGAAAAACCCUAUAAAUGUGAAGAAUGUGGAAAAGCCUUUAAUCAAUCCUAUCAACUUACUAGACAUAAGAUAGUUCAUACUAAAGAGAAACUCAACAAAUGUGAAGAAUUUGGCAAGGCCUUUAAACAGUCCUCACACCGUACUAUACAUAAAAUUAUUCAUACUGGAGAGAAACCCUACAAAUGUGAAGAACAUGGCAAAGUUUUUAACCAGUCCUCAAACCUUACUACACAAAAGAUAAUUCAUACUGGAGAGAACCUCUACAAAUUUGAAGAACAUGGAAAAGCUUUUAACCUAUUCUCAAACAUUACUAACCAUAAGAUAAUUUAUACUGGAGAGAAACCCCACAAAUGUGAAGAAUGUGGAAAAGCUUAUAACCGAUUCUCAAACCUAACUAUACAUAAGAGAAUUCAUACGGGAGAGAAACCUUACCAAUGUGCAGAAUGUGGCAAAGCCUUUAACUGCUCCUCAACCCUUAAUAGACAUAAGAUAAUUCAUACUGGAGAGAAACCUUACAAAUGUAAAGAAUGUGGCAAAGCUUUUAACCUAUCCUCAACCCUUACUGCACAUAAGAAAAUUCAUACUGGAGAGAAACCCUAUAAAUGUGAAGAAUGUGGCAAAGCUUUUAACCAAUCCUCAAACCUUACUACACAUAAGAAAAUUCAUACUUCAGAGAAACCCUACAAAUGUGAAGAAUGUGGCAAAUCCUUUAACCAGUUCUCAUCUCUUAAUAUACAUAAGAUAAUUCAUACUGGAGAGAAACCCUACAAAUGUGGAGAUUAUGGCAGAGCUUUCAACCUAUCCUCAAAUCUUACUACACAUAAGAAAAUUCAUACUGGAGAGAAACCCUACAAAUGUGAGUAUGGCAAAACUUAAUUGAUCCUACAAGCUUACUACACAUAGGAAAAUUCAUACUGGAGAGAAACUACAAAUGUGAAGAAUGUGUUAAAGCCUUUAACAAGUCUUCAACUUUUUCUGCACACACGAGGUAUUUUAUACUGGUGAGAAACCUUACAAUGUAAAGAAUGUGGCACAGCUUUUAACUAAUCUUCAAACCUUACUGAAAGUUGAGAAAAUUCGUACUGGAGAGAAUCCUACAAAUGUGAAAAAUGUGGCAAAUCCUUUAACUGAUCCUCAACUUUUACUAAACAUAAGGUAAUUCAUACUGGAGAAAAGCCAUACAAAUGAGAAGAAUGUGGCAAUGCCUUUAAUCAGUCCUCACACCUUUCUACACAUAAGAUAAUUUAUACUGGAGAGGAACUCUAUAGUUGUGAAGAAUGUGGCAAAGCUUUUAACCAAUCCUCAUACCUUACUAUACAGAAAUUCAUACUGGAGAGAAAGCCUACAAUUGUGAAGAAUGUGGCAAAGCUUUUAACCUUCCUUAACCCUUAACUGUAGAUAAGAAAAUUCAUACUGGAAAGAAACCCUACAAAUGUGAAGUCUGUGGCAAAGCUUUUAACUGAUUCUCAACUCUUACUACAUGUAAGAGUAUUUAUACUGGAAAGAAACCCUACAAAUGUAAAAAACGUGGCAAUGCCUUUAACUGGUCCUCACACCUUGCUACAUAUAAGACAGUUUAUACUUUGAGAGAAACCCUGCAAAUGUGAAUAAUGUGGCAAUACUUUAAACCAAUCCUCAAACCUCACUAAACAUAAGAUAAUACUGAAAACUUUACAAACCUGAAUGAUGUGACAAUAAUUUUGACAACACCUCGAACUUUCUAACAUAAAUCAUACUGGUGAAAAAUCCUAGAAAUGUGAAAAAUAUCACAAAGCCUUUAAAUGGUUGUCACACUUGAUUGUAGGUAAGAAUCCAUACUGAAGAAAACUCCUGGAAGUGUAAAAAAUGUGGCAACACUUUUAAUAAAUGCUCACCCCUUAUUGCACAGGAAAGCAUUUAUACUUCAGAAAGAUUGUACAAAUACAAGGAAUGUGGAAAAGCCAUUAUUAUCUGCUCAGAUUUUACUCAACAUUAGAGAGUUAGUACGUAAUAAAAGCAUUAUAAAUGCAAUUUUUGUCAAGAGAUCUUUCAGAAAAUAUAAGCCUUUAAAGUGAAGAAGAGGAGCCAGUUGUGCUGGCUCACAUCUGUAAUGCCAGCACUUUGGGAGGCCAAGGUGGGUGGAUCACCUGAGGGCAGGAGUCUGAGACCAGCCUGGCCAACAUAGCAAAACCCCAUCUCUAUUAAAAAUUUUACAAAAAUUAGCUGCGUGUGGUGGCAGGCCCCUGUAAUCCCAGCUAAUUGGGAGGCUGAAGCAGGAGAAUUGCUCAAACCUGGGAGGCGAAGAUUGCAGUGAGCUGAAAUCACACCACUACACUCCAGCCAAAGCAACAAGAGCAAAAACUUCGUCUCAAAAACAAAACAAAAAAAGAGUAUUCAUUGUGAGGACAAACAAUACAAAUACGAAGAGGGUUGUAGUACCUUUACUUGUAUCACAGAUACUUUUGUACCCAUUUUGCACUAGAGGAAAACCAUGAAGCAGUUGCUCAAAUGUUGUUCAACACCAGAAAAUUUAUAUUGGAGAAAAGCACUGUAAAUGUAAUGCAUUUGUGAAAACAUUUUUUAAAAAACUACAGCUUAGAAAAUACCAGAGGCCUCAUACUAAAAUAUAUUUUUGCAAGUGAAGUAAAUAUAAAAAUAAUUUAAUCCAAAAUUAAGUCUAUAUAAAUAUCAGAGAAUUCACAGUAGAAAUAUCUAAGGUACUGACACUUCAGACAUUGCUGAGUAUAGAAUCAGAAUGCUGAGUAUAGAAAAUAAUUUAAAACUAAAGUUGGUAGGUAAAUAAUGUGUAUAUAACUUUAAAAGAAGUAGAAUUUUUUUGUAGAUGUAUAAUUACAUUCAAAUUAUAUUUUUUCUUGAAAAAUUAGUUUUUGAAAAGCAAAUGAUGUAAUUCAACUCAAAUUCAUGCUCUUCAUUCCUAUUGUAUUCACAUGUGAAAGCAUGUGAUUAAUUUUUCAUGCAUCAAAGAUAUGAGAAAUCAUUUCUGUUAGGUCGGUAUUAUUUAUGACACUUUCUAUGAAAGAAUAAGGACAUUAAAAUGUAAGAUGCAUGAUGAAAACCUGAGUGAAGAGGCUGUUUGUGUUUAACUUAUAAUAUUGAGUGAUCCAUGAAGUAGGUUUUCAGAGCAAUAUUCUUCUGCAUUAUAGUAAGAGAAAACCAUUUUUAAUCUUAGUUAAAAUUAAAGUGAAUUAGUAGUAUAUCAUUUUACUAUUUGUACUUUUAUGUAAUAAAAUGCAAUGUGUUUAAAAAUUUUUGGAUUAUGCGUGAACUUAGUUUUUUAAUUAAACUUUUUUUAACAUGUUAAAACUAUUGUGCAUUCAAUGAAGUGUUUUCAUGCCACUGACUUUACCUAUCCCACAUUACUCAAGGGUUUAGGUAAAAGAGGGUAACAGUAUACUACUUGAUAACAUAAUGGGCUAACAUCUCUAAUAAUUAUUUUUGCUAGUGACUUUAAACUGCUAAUAAAGAAUAUUGUUCCCAUAGGUUAGAUUUUUAUUCUUUUUAAAAUUUAAACUUAUUUCUCUUAAUUUUUGUGGAUACAUAGUAUGUGUAUAUCUUUAUGCCAUGUAUGGCAUAUUUUGAUACAGGCAUAUAAUUUUAUGUAUUAAUCACAUCAGGGCAAAAGAUGUAUCCAUCAACUCCAGCAUUUCUCCUUUGUAUUACAAACCAAUUCUGCACUUUUAGAUACUUUAGAAUGUACAGUCGUUACUACAGGGUCAUUUUAUGGUUAUAAUAAAAAUUAUAUACAAGUAUAAAUAAACCAUGAGAAAAUUCUGAGUUCUGAAUAAACAUUUAAAAAA